AGAAAACAGAAAAUCUGAUUUACUUCUGGUUCCAAGCAUUUCAGAUAAGGGACACUCUACCUUUAAUUAGUUAUAAAGGAAUUAGGAGACACAUUAAGAAGCAAAAGAGCCAGUGGACAAGAUGGGCUGUCUCUUGUCCUGAGCCUUCAUUUAGAAAUAUAAUUGGGUAGACUUGCUCUGGAGGCGAAGUUCAGGUCGUUAUUGUUCUCUGUGUAUAGAGGUGGAUUUUGAGGAAUAUUUGGAGAGGAAAGGGAGCUGUGUUGGCAGAUGACAUGCAGGAAGUGUAGUUCUAGCUUGUGAGGGUUGGCCCUUUCCCAAACUAACCUAUUCUUUUUGGCACCUAGCACCUUCAAUAUGCUCCUUAGCUCUUGUGACUCGUCUGUGGUCCUAAUAUGCCUUGUGGCCCAGGCCUAACGCAGCACUAACAGUCAUACAGCCCAGUGCAACUAGGAGUUUCCAGCAGAGAUUCAGCAACCUGAAGUUAUCCUGGGUGAAAUUGCAGUUUGCCUUUACAAGAAGGUGCCCUUGCUUAAUAUGUGAUGACAUAGGGACCUUAGCAUCACAAUAAGUGACCAUUUCAUAACAAAGAAAUGAACACAUAAUAGUUGACGUUAAAAUUGGUAGCUAAACAGAACUAGGUCUGCAUGUGUCUAUUUAGCAGGGGACGGGGAGAUGAAAGUUGUUAGGAUAAUUUUUACUCUUACUUGUUCAAGAUUGUUAGCAUAUAUGUAUGCAUUUAUUGCCUGCCUUGUUCCAAAAGGAUUUAAGGAAGCUCCCUCCCACCCCCAUCACAGAAAGUAGAAUAAAACAAGAACCACAUGAGAUACUUUCUAGUUGGGAGCAAUAAUGCAGAAACGAAAUAUCGUGUCUUGAAGAUUGAUAGAACAGAACCAAAAGAUUUGGUCAUAAUUGAUGACAGGCAUGUCUAUACUCAACAAGAAGUAAGGGAACUUCUUGGCCGCUUGGAUCUUGGAAAUAGAACAAAGAUGGGACAGAAAGGAUCCUCGGGCUUAUUUCGAGCGGUUUCAGCUUUUGGUGUUGUGGGUUUUGUCAGGUUCUUAGAAGGCUAUUAUAUUGUGUUAAUAACUAAAAGGAGGAAGAUGGCGGAUAUUGGAGGUCAUGCAAUCUAUAAGGUCGAAGAUACAAAUAUGAUCUAUAUACCCAAUGAUUCUGUACGGGUUACUCAUCCUGAUGAAGCUAGGUAUCUACGAAUAUUUCAAAAUGUGGACCUAUCUAGCAAUUUUUACUUUAGUUACAGCUAUGAUUUGUCCCACUCACUUCAAUAUAAUCUCACUGUCUUGCGAAUGCCCCUGGAGAUGUUAAAGUCAGAAAUGACCCAGAAUCGCCAAGAGAGCUUUGACAUCUUUGAAGAUGAAGGAUUAAUUACACAAGGUGGAAGCGGGGUAUUUGGGAUCUGUAGUGAGCCUUAUAUGAAAUAUGUAUGGAAUGGUGAACUUCUGGAUAUAAUUAAAAGUACUGUGCAUCGUGACUGGCUUUUGUAUAUUAUUCAUGGGUUCUGUGGGCAGUCAAAGCUGUUGAUCUAUGGACGACCAGUGUAUGUCACUCUAAUAGCUAGAAGAUCCAGUAAAUUUGCUGGCACCCGUUUUCUUAAAAGAGGUGCAAACUGUGAGGGUGAUGUUGCAAAUGAAGUGGAGACUGAACAAAUACUCUGCGAUGCUUCUGUGAUGUCUUUCACUGCAGGAAGUUAUUCUUCAUAUGUACAAGUUAGAGGAUCUGUGCCCUUAUACUGGUCUCAGGACAUUUCAACUAUGAUGCCUAAACCACCUAUUACAUUGGAUCAGGCAGAUCCAUUUGCACAUGUGGCUGCCCUUCACUUUGACCAGAUGUUCCAGAGGUUUGGCUCUCCCAUCAUCAUCUUGAAUUUAGUGAAGGAACGAGAGAAAAGAAAGCAUGAAAGAAUUCUGAGUGAAGAACUUGUUGCUGCUGUGACCUAUCUCAACCAAUUUUUGCCUCCUGAGCACACUAUUGUUUAUAUUCCCUGGGACAUGGCCAAGUAUACCAAAAGCAAGCUGUGUAAUGUUCUUGAUCGACUAAAUGUGAUUGCAGAAAGUGUGGUGAAGAAAACAGGUUUCUUUGUAAACCGCCCUGAUUCUUACUGUAGCAUUUUGCGGCCAGAUGAAAAGUGGAAUGAACUAGGAGGAUGUGUGAUUCCCACUGGUCGCCUGCAGACUGGCAUCCUUCGAACCAACUGUGUGGACUGUUUAGAUCGCACCAACACAGCACAGUUUAUGGUGGGAAAAUGUGCUCUGGCCUAUCAGCUGUAUUCACUGGGACUGAUUGACAAACCUAAUCUACAGUUUGAUACAGAUGCAGUUAGGUUAUUUGAGGAACUCUAUGAAGAUCAUGGUGAUACCCUAUCCCUUCAGUAUGGUGGUUCUCAACUUGUUCAUCGUGUGAAAACCUACAGAAAGAUAGCACCAUGGACCCAGCACUCCAAAGACAUCAUGCAAACCCUGUCUAGAUAUUACAGCAAUGCUUUUUCAGAUGCCGAUAGACAAGAUUCCAUUAAUCUCUUCCUGGGAGUUUUCCAUCCCACUGAAGGGAAACCUCAUCUCUGGGAGCUCCCAACAGAUUUUUAUUUGCAUCACAAAAAUACCAUGAGACUUUUGCCAACAAGAAGAAGUUAUACUUACUGGUGGACACCAGAGGUGAUAAAGCAUUUACCAUUGCCCUAUGAUGAAGUUAUCUGUGCUGUGAACUUAAAGAAGUUGAUAGUGAAGAAAUUCCACAAAUAUGAAGAAGAGAUUGAUAUCCACAAUGAGUUCUUUCGGCCAUAUGAGUUGAGCAGCUUUGAUGAUACCUUUUGCUUGGCUAUGACAAGCUCAGCACGUGACUUUAUGCCUAAGACCGUUGGAAUUGAUCCAAGUCCAUUUACUGUGCGUAAACCAGAUGAAACUGGAAAAUCAGUAUUGGGAAACAAAAGCAAUAGAGAAGAAGCUGUAUUACAGCGGAAAACGGCAGCCAGCGCCCCGCCGCCCCCCAGCGAGGAGGCUGUGUCCAGCAGCUCUGAGGAUGACUCUGGGACUGAUCGGGAAGAAGAGGGCUCUGUGUCUCAGCGCUCCACUCCCGUGAAGAUGACUGAUGCAGGAGACAGUGCCAAAGUGACCGAGAAUGUGGUCCAACCCAUGAAGGAGCUAUAUGGAAUUAACCUCUCAGAUGGCCUCUCAGAAGAAGAUUUCUCCAUUUAUUCAAGAUUUGUUCAGCUGGGGCAGAGUCAACAUAAACAAGACAAGAAUAGCCAGCAGCCCUGUUCUAGGUGCUCAGAUGGAGUUAUAAAACUAACACCCAUCUCGGCUUUCUCGCAAGAUAACAUCUAUGAAGUUCAGCCCCCAAGAGUAGACAGAAAAUCUACAGAGAUCUUCCAAGCCCACAUCCAGGCCAGCCAAGGUAUCAUGCAGCCCCUAGGAAAAGAGGACUCCUCCAUGUACCGAGAGUACAUCAGGAACCGCUACCUGUGAAAAGAGCGCAGGUCCACCUGGUGGACACGUCUGAUUAGCUUAGAACCUGUCUUGUCUCAUCUUCAAAAGGUAACUUAUUAAAAGUCCUUUGCGUCUGAAGCCUUUCUCCUUUUCUGUCACUUGCAAAUUCCAAAUUAUAGCUAAUAAAGAUGACUAGAUAA